CUUCCUCCUCCCCGAGUCCUAGCCGACGCCGCCGCCGCCGCGCGCGCGGGGCCUGGAACACACGGCACGAGCCGCCCCCGCCCCUCCCCCCUUACGCCCACGCGGAGCCGGCCCCGCGCGCGCGCGCGUGUCCCGUGCAUCCCCGCGCCUGCGCGCUGCCCAGGCCCUGCCCGUGUGUGGGGGUCGCUGCCGGCCCCGGGGGGGGGUGGGGAAAAUAAGGGAUUAAAAAAACAGCGCGCGGAACCGGGCCAGGGUUGCCCACCCCCGCCACAAUGGCCUCUGGGGUGGAAGUCCUGCGCUUCCAGCUGCCCGGCCACGAGGCCGCAACGCUACGGAACAUGAACCAGCUCCGGGCAGAGGAGCGGUUCUGCGACGUGACCAUUGUGGCCGACAGCCUCAAGUUUCGAGGCCACAAGGUCAUCUUGGCCGCCUGCUCACCCUUCCUGCGGGACCAGUUCCUGCUGAACCCCAGCUCGGAGCUGCAGGUCUCCCUGAUGCACAGUGCACGCAUCGUGGCCGACUUGCUCCUCUCCUGCUACACGGGCGCCUUGGAAUUCGCUGUUAGGGACAUCGUCAACUACCUUACAGCCGCCUCCUACCUGCAGAUGGAGCACGUGGUGGAGAAAUGCCGGAAUGCCCUCAGCCAGUUCAUUGAGCCCAAAAUAGGCCUCAAAGAGGAUGGGGUCAGUGAGGCUAGCCUUGUGAGCAGCAUCAGCGCCACCAAGUCCCUCCUCCCUCCAGCCAGGACCCCAAAGCCAGCCCCGAAGCCCCCACCCCCACCUCCUCUACCCCCUCCACUCCUGCGGCCAGUGAAGCUGGAGUUCCCACUGGAUGAAGACUUGGAGCUGAAAGCCGAGGAAGAGGAUGAGGAUGAGGAUGAGGACGUGUCUGACAUCUGCAUCGUCAAGGUGGAGUCGGCCCUGGAGGUGGCACACCGGCUCAAACCCCCUGGAGGCCUGGGAGGGGGUCUGGGCAUUGGAGGCUCCGUGGGUGGCCACCUUGGGGAGCUGGCCCAGAGCAGCGUUCCCCCCAGCACUGUAGCCCCACCGCAGGGUGUGGUGAAGGCCUGCUAUAGCCUGUCGGAAGAUGCAGAAGGGGAGGGCCUGCUGUUGAUUCCCGGAGGCCGGGCCAGCGUGGGGGCCACCUCGGGCCUGGUGGAAGCAGCAGCGGUGGCCAUGGCUGCCCGGGGGGCGGGGGGCAGCCUGGGGGCGGGGGGCAGCCGGGGACCCCUGCCUGGGGGCUUCUCAGGUGGAAACCCCUUAAAGAACAUCAAGUGCACGAAGUGCCCGGAAGUGUUCCAGGGCGUGGAGAAGCUGGUCUUCCACAUGCGGGCGCAGCACUUCAUCUUCAUGUGCCCUCGCUGUGGCAAGCAGUUCAACCACAGCAGCAACCUCAACCGCCACAUGAACGUGCAUCGUGGUGUCAAGUCACACUCGUGCGGCAUCUGCGGCAAGUGCUUCACACAGAAGUCCACCCUUCACGACCACCUCAACCUGCACUCGGGAGCGCGGCCCUACCGCUGCUCCUACUGCGACGUGCGCUUCGCCCACAAGCCUGCCAUUAGGCGGCACCUCAAGGAGCAACACGGCAAGACCACGGCCGAGAACGUGCUGGAGGCCAGUGUGGCCGAGAUUAACGUCCUCAUCCGCUAGCCGCGCAGGCGUGGAGGCCAGGAGGCUGGGGCCCCUGGGCUGCGUGGAAAAAGGGCUCUUUGGCCCAGGAGAAUUGGGGGGUGGGGGGUCUGGGGCAGAAAGGUAAGAGUGGGAGGCUGAGCAGAUGCACACAUCCUGAGAGAGGGAAGAUGAUUCCUUGGAGAGACUUGCUCUUGAGAGUGCAAGAAUCUGGAGCUGGGAAAAGGGUUCUUGGAGGCCAGGGGAAUACGGGGUCCCAGAGAAAGAUUUCCUUCUCUUAGAAGUGCAUGUAUAUGUGGAGGGAGGGAAAAGGGUCCUAUAGAAUGAGGGAAGA